CUUUUCUCUGACAGCAUCUGUCUCUAAAGGCCGAACAACGGGAGAUGCAGCGGAAUUGGAUUAAAAGACUCUGAAAGUACAGUCGUUCAUCUUUAUAUUAAGAUAAUAUUUUCUGAUAGGAAACGACUAUUUAACAUGGAUUAUCACUGGCGAGGAGAGCUGGGAUCCUGGCGACUACUACUCUUGCUUCUGCUCCUCGCAGCCUGGAAGGUGGGGAGCGGCCAGCUCCACUACUCCGUCCCCGAGGAGGCCAAACACGGCACCUUCGUGGGCCGGAUCGCGCAGGACCUGGGGCUGGAGCUGGCGGAGCUGGUGCCGCGCCUGUUCCGGGUGGCGUCCAAAAGACACCGGGACCUUCUGGAGGUAAGUCUGCAGAAUGGCAUUUUGUUUGUGAAUUCUCGGAUCGACCGCGAGGAGCUGUGCGGGCGGAGCGCGGAGUGCAGCAUCCACCUGGAGGUGAUCGUGGACAGGCCGCUGCAGGUUUUCCAUGUGGACGUGGAGGUGAAGGAUGUUAAUGACAACCCGCCAGUGUUCCGGGUAAAAGACCAAAAGCUGUUUGUUUCAGAAUCCAGAAUGCCAGACUCUCGGUUUCCGCUAGAGGGCGCGUCCGAUGCAGAUGUUGGAGCUAACUCCGUGUUAACCUACAGGCUUAGCUCUCAUGAUUACUUCAUGCUAGAUGUGAAUUCAAAGAACGAUGAGAAUAAACUGGUUGAGCUCGUAUUAAGAAAAUCCUUGGACAGAGAGGACGCUCCUGCGCACCACUUAUUCCUGACAGCCACAGAUGGGGGCAAACCUGAGCUCACAGGCACUGUUCAGCUGCUGGUCACAGUGCUGGAUGUGAAUGAUAAUGCUCCCACUUUCGAACAGUCUGAAUACGAAGUAAGAAUAUUCGAAAACGCAGACAACGGAACAACAGUUAUCAAACUGAAUGCUUCUGAUCCGGAUGAAGGAGCCAAUGGGGCAAUUUCAUAUUCUUUUAAUAGCCUUGUUGAAACUAUGGUUAUUGACCACUUUAGCAUAGAUCGAAAUACGGGAGAAAUAGUGAUUCGGGGUAAUUUGGAUUUUGAACAAGAAAACUUAUACAAAAUCCUCAUUGACGCCACGGACAAAGGCCAUCCUCCCAUGGCGGGUCAUUGCACCGUUUUAGUGAGAAUUUUGGAUAAAAAUGAUAACGUCCCUGAGAUAGCACUGACUUCCUUAUCCUUGCCUGUACGUGAAGACGCUCAAUUUGGUACUGUCAUCGCCCUAAUUAGCGUGAACGACCUCGAUUCAGGUGCCAACGGGCAGGUGACCUGCUCCCUGAUGCCCCAUGUCCCCUUCAAGCUGGUGUCCACCUUCAAGAAUUACUACUCGUUGGUGCUGGACAGCGCCCUGGACCGCGAGAGAGUGUCGGCCUAUGAGUUGGUGGUAACCGCGCGGGACGGGGGCUCGCCUUCGCUGUGGGCCACCGCCAGCUUGUCUGUGGAGGUGGCCGACGUGAACGACAAUGCUCCGGCGUUCGCGCAGCCCGAGUACACGGUGUUCGUGAAGGAGAACAACCCGCCGGGCUGCCACAUCUUCACGGUGUCUGCGCGAGACGCGGACGCGCAGGAGAACGCGCUGGUGUCCUACUCGCUUGUGGAGCGGCGGGUGGGCGAGCGCUCGCUGUCGAGCUACAUUUCGGUGCACACGGAGAGCGGCAAGGUGUACGCGCUGCAGCCGCUGGACCACGAGGAGCUAGAGCUGCUGCAGUUCCAGGUGAGCGCGCGCGACGCGGGCGUGCCGCCUCUGGGCAGCAACGUGACGCUGCAGGUGUUCGUGCUGGACGAGAAUGACAACGCGCCGGCACUGCUGGAGCCUCGGGUGGGUGGCACUGGUGGCGCAGCGAGCAAGCUGGUGCCGCGGUCUGUGGGCGCGGGCCACGUGGUAGCGAAGGUGCGCGCAGUGGACGCCGACUCGGGCUACAACGCGUGGCUUUCGUAUGAGCUGCAGCCAGCUGCAAGCAGCCCUCGCAUCCCGUUCCGCGUGGGGCUGUACACGGGCGAGAUCAGCACCACUCGUGUCCUGGACGAAGCGGACUCUCCGCGCCACCGUCUGCUGGUCCUGGUGAAGGAUCAUGGUGAACCUGCGCUGACCGCCACGGCCACGGUUCUGGUGUCGCUGGUGGAGAGCGGCCAGGCUCCAAAAGCGUCAUCGAGGCAGUCGGCUGGCGUUUUGGGUCCGGAAGCGGCGCUGGUGGAUGUCAACGUGUACCUGAUCAUCGCCAUCUGCGCGGUAUCCAGCCUGCUGGUGCUCACGCUGCUGCUGUACACUGCGCUGCGGUGCUCAGCACUGCCCACUGAGGGCGGGUGCCGGGCGGGCAAGCCCACUCUGGUGUGCUCCAGUGCGGUGGGGAGCUGGUCAUACUCGCAACAACAGCCGCAGAGGGUGUGCUCUGGUGAGGGGCCACCGAAGACGGACCUCAUGGCCUUCAGCCCCUGCCUUCCUCCUGAUCUGGGAUCAGUUGAUGUAGGCGAAGAGCAAGAUUUAAAUGUUGAUCAUGGCCUCAAACCACGACAGCCCAACCCUGACUGGCGUUACUCUGCCUCCCUGAGAGCAGGCAUGCACAGCUCUGUGCACCUAGAGGAGGCUGGCAUUCUACGGGCUGGUCCAGGAGGGCCUGAUCAGCAGUGGCCAACAGUAUCCAGUGCAACACCAGAACCAGAGGCAGGAGAAGUGUCCCCUCCAGUCGGUGCGGGUGUCAACAGCAACAGCUGGACCUUUAAAUACGGACCAGGCAACCCCAAACAAUCCGGUCCCGGUGAGUUGCCCGACAAAUUCAUUAUCCCAGGAUCUCCUGCAAUCAUCUCCAUCCGGCAGGAGCCUACUAACAGCCAAAUUGACAAAAGUGACUUCAUAACCUUCGGCAAAAAGGAGGAGACCAAGAAAAAGAAGAAAAAGAAGAAGGGUAACAAGACCCAGGAGAAAAAAGAGAAAGGGAACAGCACGACUGACAACAGUGACCAGUGAGGUCCUCAAAUGGAAACAAGCCACUUAGCCAGUUUUUGUAAUAAUGGCAAAUCUCUCCCAUGUAGCAAUUCCCUGCUCCUUUUUCCUAUCUACAUGAGCCCUCUUAGAGACCUCAGAAAUCUGCAGAAAGUUCCCUGUGUCUGUCUAGAACGCAUUUAACAGGUUUUGUCGUAAAAGCUUUACUAAGUCUGGUGUUAACUCUUUCUCUCCACUCUGGCUUGUUUUCAGAACCUAAAAAGCAGACCCAAGUUUCCUUUCUCCUCCGCCGCAAAGGAGAGGCUUCCCAGCCCCGCCAGUGAGAGGUUGGACUCUCUGCCCUGUGCUCCGGGGAUCCUGUCUUGAUGACACUUGCAGGGCAGGCUGAAAAGUUUUGAGAUUGAGCAGCUUGGGAGUUUGUGGCCACUGGGUAUGUGUGGCUACCGCGGGUAUGCGAGUGCCAGAUAUUGGCUGAGACGAGCCAGCUUAGACUAAUUGGUACAAGGAAGGCAAGAAAACAAAGACAAAUAAACAGCGGAAGUUAUCAGUAUGGAGGGGAAGUGUAAACUUAAAGGGACCAGACUUUCUAAAUCUUACAACUCAAGAGGUGGCAGCCACCCUCUAGGAGACAAAACUACCCCCACUGACAAGGCUUUAGGAGACCCUAAAGUCUGUUGGCUGUGACGUCAUUAUACCUAAAAUCUGCAUCAUACCUGCAAGCCAACAGUUCAGUGUUUUAACAGAGAACCACCCUGGGAAACAGAAGCAGAUCUGAUGUGUUUCCUAUACAUGUCCUGUGCUCACUUUAUUAAAAAUUCUUUUGCACACAAUGUUUAUGAAAAGGCCAGAUCCUUUUCCAAUACUUAUGCAAAAGCAAAAGAAAACCCCGACACCUCACCUUUCGCUGUUUGUUGUUUCAUAGAUUUAUUUAAAAAAAGAGAAAGUCUAUAGCUAUAAAUCUUUAAAGAGAAAUAUGAAUACAAUUCCCCUAAACUCUCCUCAAAAGAGAAUUCAGUCUACAGCCAUUUAAAUGAUCAUUGCUGCUACAGAAGUGCUUUAAGAGAAUUGCCUGAAACAUCUGUAUUAUAUCGGCCACCUGCCAAUCACAGCUUUACUCUUUCAGGUCACUCUGGGGCUGCCUCUUGCAUGUAUUACUAAAUAAAAUGAUCUCUCUUUCUCUCUCUCUCUCUCUUUUCUAAGAAACAAUUAUGUGCACUUUGAUACACAACCUUCUCUAACCAACUAUAUAUCAAGACCCAAAAAUUGAAGAAAAAUAUUGUUUUCUCAUACAGUGAGCAGAUUUUUCAAUCUACUAAUUCUGUGACUUGUCUUGGUGUGCUAGCCUACACCUUCUCUUUGGUUUAGUUUUCCUUUUCUAUAACACUCUGAAUUGCUAAUCUUACUAACACCUAUGAUGUUACCUGAAAUCAAUCUCCCAUAUGUAUGCUGUAUGCUAUGCUAAGACUCCUGAAAUAUACUUACUCUGUGCUUGUGUAUGUGAAUGUUAAUGCAACUAUUACCUAGAGUGAACUUUAAGCUUUAUUGUUGAAUGUAAUUCCAUUAUAUUUCCUUUUGUACACCUGUGAAAAAGUGGAGUAGUGUUUUUUUAACCAUUGUUAAUCAGCUUUUGUGUAUGAAAGACACAGUAAAAUUUCUUUCUUAAAUCAAGAUACUGGUGAUUCAAGGAAUUUUAUUUAUGGUCCAGCCAAGAGCCAUCUCGUGCCAAGACUUCUGCUGGCAAGGGAAUGGAUAAAGCUGUUUUGUUCUAGUAACAAUUUUGGAAUGAAUACUGACAAUAUUCCAUGAGGGUGUGCAAGCACAAAUUUUACCAAUCUGACCUCUUUGAAGUUGCAGAAUGCUUUGAAAUUCUAAUGGUAUCUGAAAUAUCAGCUCAUAGAAAGUAACAAAAUUUGCUGUCACCUUAAAUAAGACAUUUUAAUUUUGUUAUAAUGUACAAUUUAGAAGUUUGAUUAAUUAUAUUAUCUAUUUAGGCAUUAAUAUAAAAGAGGUAGGAGUCUGUUAUUUAAAAAAAGCAUUAAAUUUAAAAAAAAACUGUCUUGUCUACUUUUAGCUUCAUUCUCCCAUAUUUUGAAGGGUGUGUAACUUCAGCUCUGCAGGAUUGCAUGGGGUAAAACUUGUUACCAACACAUGUGAACCAUUGCUACAUUGUAGGUUGUGAUCAUUUUGCCCCACUGAAGCCCAUGUAUCUGACCUUACGUGCCUUUUGAACUAGGAGAAUCGGGCUAAUUUAUUAAUGAUGAUAAUUAUAAUGUAUCUGUACAGCACUUUUUACAUUUGCGAAGUGCUUUCCAAUCCAUGUUAGUUACUAGUUAUUACAGCUGUAAGGAUAAAACACGUCAUGUGGAUUCAUUUUGAAUUGGUGCUAUUGGUAUUUCCUCUGUUAUUGCUAAUAAAUGAAAAUGGUGGUAUGAAA